ACCUUUCAAAGGUUCUCCAGCAGUAUUUAACUGAUGCAAAAGGAACACACUUGCAAUUUUCUACUUUUGACAUGACAGACCCUCCUCUUAGUUCACACAAUGUUCAAAAGGCACAAGUCCCUCGCUUCGGAACGCAAGAGAGCAUUACUUUCCCAAAGAGCUACACGGUUCAUACUGAAGGAUGAUAUGAGAAAUUUUCACUUUUUGUCAAAACUUGUACUCUCAGCGGGCCCUCUAAGACCAACUCCAGCAGUCAAACAUUCAAAAACGACUCACUUUGAGAUUGAAAUAUUUGAUGCUCAAACAAGGAAACAGAUAUGUAUUCUGGAUAAGGUGACACAAUCAUCUACUAUUCAUGAUGUUAAGCAAAAGUUUCACAAAGCAUGUCCAAAGUGGUACCCUUCUCGAGUUGGUCUGCAGCUAGAAUGUGGCGGGCCUUUUUUGAAGGACUACAUUACCAUUCAAAGUAUUGCAGCUUCCUCCAUUGUCACACUGUAUGCUACAGACCUAGGUCAACAAGUCAGUUGGACCACAGUGUUUUUGGCUGAAUACACAGGACCUCUGCUAAUAUACCUCCUCUUUUAUUUGAGGAUCCCAUGUAUAUAUGAUGGAAAAGAGAGUGCUAGAAGAUUACGCCACCCAGUGGUACACUUGGCUUGCUUCUGUCAUUGUAUACACUACAUCCGAUACCUUUUGGAAACCUUAUUUGUUCACAAAGUUUCUGCAGGACACACACCUUUGAAAAAUUUGAUAAUGAGUUGUGCCUUUUACUGGGGAUUUACUUCUUGGAUUGCCUACUACAUUAAUCAUCCACUAUAUACACCACCAUCAUUUGGAAACAGGCAAAUCACAGUAUCUGCUAUCAAUUUUCUGAUUUGUGAAGCUGGGAAUCAUUUCAUCAAUGUAAUGUUGUCUCAUCCCAAUCACACAGGAAACAAUGCCUGUUUCCCAAGUCCAAAUUAUAACCCCUUCACAUGGAUGUUUUUCCUGGUUUCAUGUCCUAACUACACCUAUGAGAUUGGAUCAUGGAUUAGUUUCACAGUCAUGACACAAACACUGCCAGUUGGAAUUUUUACACUUCUGAUGAGUAUCCAGAUGUCUUUGUGGGCACAAAAGAAACAUAAGAUUUAUCUGAGAAAAUUCAAUUCAUAUAUUCAUAGAAAAUCAGCAAUGAUUCCAUUCAUAUUGUAAAAAAAGAAUCUUAUCUCCUAUAGAAAACAGCAACAUAUAAAUUCAAUAAAUAAGACUUAGUUAAGGAUAGUUAACUAUUAUACUCCAACAAUUCAUGAGCAACAGUAUAUACACUGAGUAAAAAUAUAAAAUAGUAAAAUUUCACUAAAUUUAGAGAAAUGCACAUGGUAAUAAAAAGUAUAAAUUAUAAAUGCAAUUAACUAAGAACAGCUCUGAAUGUAUUUGCAUGGGAUUGGUCCUUGAAUAAAAUUGUCUUACUUCAUUAAUACUUCACAAUACUAUUUGCAUAAGACAAAAUACCACAGCAAAAAAAAAAAUCUGAUUAACAAAUGAAAAAGCGAUCUGAACAGACAUUUCCCAAAGGAAGACAUAUACAUGGUCAAUAAGUAUAUUUUUAAAAUGCUCAACAUUAACUAUUCAUACAGAAAUGCAAAUCAAAACCACAAUGAGAUAUCAUCUCAUCCUAAUUAAGGUGACUAUUUUCAAAAAGACAAAAAAUAUGACAGCCGUGGUGGUUCAUAUCUGUAAUCCUAACACUUUGACAGGCCAAGGCAGGGGAAUUGCUUGAGUUCAGAAGUUUGAGAUCUGGGCAACAUAUUGAGACUCUGUCUCUAAAAAGCAUAUUGAGACUCUGUCUCUACAAAAAAAUUUUAAAAAGUAAAAAUUAGCUGGGCGUGGUGGCACAUGCCAGUAGGUAGUCCCAGCUACUCGAGGUUGCUCCAGCUCAGGCGUUCAAGGCUACAGAGAGCCAUGAUUAAACCAAGGCACUCCAGCCUGGGUGACAGAGUGAGACUGUCUCAAAAUAAAAUAAAAAUAACAUAUUGGUGAAGAUGCGGGAAAAAAAAAAGAACUCUUAGACACUGCUGGUGGGAAUGUAAACUAGAGCAGCCAUGUGGAGAACAACAUGGACUUUCUUCAAAAAUUACAAAUAGAACUAUCAUAUGAUCCAGCAAUACCAUUACUGGAAAAAGGAAAUCUGUAUAUUAAAGAGACAUUUGAACCCUAUGUUUACUGCAGCACUAUUCACAAUAGCCAAGAUAUAGGAGCAACCUAGGUGUCCAACAACAGAUGAAUGGAUAAAGAAAAUGUGGUAUAUAUACACAAUAGAAUACUAUGCAGCCAUAAAAACUGAAUUCCUGUCAUUCAGGACAACAUGGAUGGAAUUGGAGGGCAUAUGUUAAGUGAAACAAGCCAGGAACAGAAAGUUAAACAUUGCAUGUUAUUACUUAUAUGUGGAAGCUAAAAAAAUUGAUAUCAUAGAAGUAAAAAAUAAAACAGAGGAUACUACAGGCUGGGAAAGCUGCAGCAAAGGGAGACUAGAGAGAGAUUUGUUAAAGGAUACAAAGUUACAGCUUGGUAGGAGGAAUAAUUUCUGGUGUUCUAUACCACUGUAGGACGACUAUAGUUAAGAACAUUAUAUUCCAUUUAGUUUCAAAUAGCUAAAAGGAGAUUUUGUCCCCAACAAAAAGAAAUGAUAAAUAUUUGAAACCAUGGAUACUCUAAUUUCUCUGAUCUGACCACUAUAAAUUAUAUGUAUUGAAACAUUAUUAUGUAUCUCCCAAAUAUGUUCAAUUCUUAUGUCGCUCAAAAAAUAAAAUUUAAUUUAAAAAGUAUCUGAUUUUUAAAGUAAAUAUUUUUUAAAGUUUUGACAUUUAAAUUACUUGAAUCUCAUUAUUUUGACAAUAAUUUAAUUCUUUUAUUGUUCAAUCUGUUAGUGAGAUGUGUCAUAGGUAUUAUGUCAUUAGUUCAAAUUCUUGCGGAAAUUAUAGCUAUAUUAAAAGUGUAACAUUUUUAUUUAGUUGUGUACUUAUUUGUUAAUAAUACAGACAUUGUAUGUUAUCAUACUGAAAUUUACAAUUAAAAUAUUUUCUGUAGAUUAUUUGAAAAUCAUUCUAAAUAUAUAUUUUGAAAUAUAUAGAUUAUAUUUGUAUGUAAAUUAUAUUUAUACAUCUUCUGAAAUAUAUUUCAAAAUAUGUGUGUACGUGUGUAUAUGUGUAUAUAUAUACACAUAUAUAUACACAUACACAAAUAUAUGCAUAUUUCAAAUGGAUUGUAUGCACUUGCAAAGCAAAAGUACAUUGGUAAUUUGGGCACAUUCAGAGUGGAAAAAAUUUGUUCUAUUUUUACAUCUUUAAAUACCUAUCUUCUAUGAAAGCCUAUGUGCAUGUGUGUGUGUGUAUGAGUUUCUAUGUGAGCAUGCAUAUAUACUUCACAAAGAGAUGACCUAUAUAAAUCAAAGUACACAUUAUUUAAAAUAUUUAAAAAAAUUUUCAGUUUCUUCAUUUUUAAAUUGUGAUUUUUAGAUUUGUUAGUCUAUGGAGUAUUUUCAAUUCUCAGAUUAUACAUAUGUUAUAAAAUAUGUUCAUUAAA